AUAUUGUGGGCAGAUUUUACUAUUUAUGUUGGAAGUUUUACAUCAUUUAGCUCCUAUAAUUCAUAUUUAUUCAUCCUAGAUGAAAGUAGCAAUAAGCAAUAAGUAUACAGUUAACCAAACAGAAUGUUGAGUGCUGUGAAAGCAAUAAACUGCGGAGUUCCAAGGGAACCUAAAGGAGAGACACCUAAGCCAUUUGGGAAGAAUGGAAAAGCAUUUUAAAGGAAAUGAUGUCUCAGUGGUAGCCUGAGGAAAAGUCCAAGUUAUUCAGACCUGGGUUUUUGGGGAGGGACCAGAGAAUGUGGUGAGAGGAUUUGGAGAGCAUUGUAAGCAGAGGUUAUCACAGCAUAGAAUGCUUACCACCAUUUAUUGUGUUUCAGCACUGUGAUCAUUGCAUUGAAUUACAUUGUCUCGUUUAAUCUUUGCUACUAACUUGUGAGGUAUAUGUUCUCAUUUUACAAAUGAGAAAACAGAUUCCAGGACUUUCAGAUCAUACAACUCUUAAUUGACUAUUUUACAUAUCAGCUCUUCAGAAGUGGUAGCAUUUUCUUUUGCAUAUCUAGCUCAGGAGCAGCUGAAUAUAUAAGGGUUUGAGGGUGAAAAGCUUCUGGAAACUUUACACUAUUUUCUUGUCUCUUUGUGCAGGAGUCCAACAUGUACCUAUACCUCUUCCUCACACCAGUAUCUUUUAAAAUUCUAUGUGAUAGGUUGCUGUAUUGUUAAUUUUGAAAGGAUUUUCAUUGAUAACUGCACAGGGAACUGAAUUAAAUAUAUCUUUUAGUUUAGGAAAACAGUAAUGCUCAAAGCUUAUCUCUUAUCUAAGAUCAGAUAAACUAGAACUUGAGAUCUUCAUGGGCCUGCUGCCUCCUGCUUGGGCAUUCUGCAUCUCUGUAGGAUCUUCUGAUGUAGAUUUACGUGUCUGUUCGGCACUUGAAGUACUCCUUGUUUAAGAAAUCACUACUGGGCAGUGUUUCGGAUAAUGGAAUAGUAACUCUCUGGGAUGUAAAUAGUCAGAGUCCAUACCAUAACUUUGACAGUGUACACAAAGCUCCAGCGUCAGGCAUCUGUUUUUCUCCUGUCAAUGAAUUGCUCUUUGUAACCAUAGGCUUGGAUAAAAGAAUCAUCCUCUAUGACACUUCAAGUAAGAAGCUAGUGAAAACUUUAGUGGCUGACACUCCUCUAACUGCGGUAGAUUUCAUGCCUGAUGGAGCCACUUUGGCUAUUGGAUCUUCCCGGGGGAAAAUAUAUCAAUAUGAUUUAAGAAUGUUGAAAUCACCAGUUAAGACCAUCAGUGCUCACAAGACAUCUGUGCAGUGUAUAGCAUUUCAGUACUCCACUGUUCUUACUAAGUCAAGUUUAAAUAAAGGCUGUUCAAAUAAGCCCACAACAGUGAACAAACGAAGUGUUAAUGUGAAUGCUGCUAGUGGAGGAGUUCAGAAUUCCGGAAUUGUCAGAGAAGCACCUGCCACGUCCAUUGCCACAGUUCUACCACAACCUAUGACAUCAGCUAUGGGGAAAGGAACAGUUGCUGUUCAAGAAAAAGCAGGUUUGCCUCGAAGCAUAAACACAGACACUUUAUCUAAGGAAACAGACAGUGGAAAAAAUCAGGAUUUCUCCAGCUUUGAUGAUACUGGGAAAAGUAGUUUAGGUGACAUGUUCUCACCUAUCAGAGAUGAUGCUGUAGUUAACAAGGGAAGUGAUGAGUCCAUAGGCAAAGGAGAUGGCUUUGACUUUCUACCGCAGUUGAACUCAGUGUUUCCUCCAAGAAAAAAUCCAGUAACUUCAAGUACUUCAGUAUUGCAUUCUAGUCCUCUUAAUGUUUUUAUGGGAUCUCCAGGGAAAGAGGAAAAUGAAAACCGUGAUCUAACAGCUGAGUCUAAGAAAAUAUAUAUGGGAAAACAGGAAUCUAAAGACUCCUUCAAACAGUUAGCAAAGUUGGUCACAUCUGGUGCUGAAAGUGGAAAUCUAAAUACCUCUCCAUCAUCUAACCAAACAAGAAAUUCUGAGAAAUUUGAAAAGCCAGAGAAUGAAAUUGAAGCCCAGUUGAUAUGUGAACCCCCAAUCAAUGGAUCCUCAACUCCAAAUCCAAAGAUAGCAUCUUCUGUCACUGCUGGAGUUGCCAGUUCACUCUCAGAAAAAAUAGCCGACAGCAUUGGAAAUAACCGGCAAAAUGCACCAUUGACUUCCAUUCAAAUUCGUUUUAUUCAGAACAUGAUACAGGAAACGUUGGAUGACUUUAGAGAAGCAUGCCAUAGGGACAUUGUGAAUUUGCAAGUGGAGAUGAUUAAACAGUUUCAUAUGCAACUGAAUGAAAUGCAUUCUUUGCUGGAAAGAUACUCAGUGAAUGAAGGUUUAGUGGCUGAAAUUGAAAGACUACGAGAAGAAAACAAAAGAUUACGGGCCCACUUUUGAAAUUUCAGUGAAUACCUUAAUGUUCUGUAAUUUGGGAAGUUUCUGGCAACACAGAACUACAUAGAAUCAGUAUUGUUUUCAUGGCCUCCAGGGAAAAAAUGUUUUUCAAGUAAGAGUAAAAGGAUGAUGGGAUUUUAUACCAACAACUGUUUCAUCUUAAAAAUAUGUAUAUUUUUAUAUUAAAAAUUGUACAGUAUGUCAUCUACCCAAUAGGAAAGUCAACAGGAUCUUUAUUUUUUGAAAGCUUUAGCCAUCCACUAAGUGCCCUUUUUCAUAAGAGAAGAAAAUUGUGCAUAAAAAUUGGUUAUGUUUGUUUUUUAGUCAUCUUUUUUAACAUAUAUUUUUGAUUGACAAAUUGCCUUUCAAAUUUUUGGGGCUAGUUGAGAUUUAAAGAGUUUGAUAUGCCUUCUAUUUUUAUGGAGAAAGUAAUUUUAAAAUGGCAAUUGGUGUUUCUAAGCCAUUGACUAAUAAAACAUAGGGUUGGCUAGUAAUUAUUUUGUUAACUUGAUGAAGUCAAGUAUGACUAUUAUUUAUUGUACAUUUGAUAAGACAAUUUUUGGAAUUUUGAAUUGCACAAAUUACAUGAUAUCUUUUGCAUUUAUGUUACUAUAUUGUACUUCUGACAAAUCUUUAUUCCUGGGUGGUAUUUUUAAGAUAUCUUUACCUAUAAAAAAUGUUUAAGGUUCAUAGGACUCGACAAGAGCUAUCUGGUGAUUUUCUCAUUAGUAACAUGCAACGUUGUACUGCAAAAUUUCAAUCAACAUGACAACUUAUAAUGAGUGGAGAUUUCAUAUUAGGUACUAAAUAUUAUAGUAUUAUUUCUAUUUUCUUUUUCCAAAUAAGAAGCUUGGAUUAUUUUAUUUUGUGGUCUUUAUCAUUAACUUUAAUUCUUUCUGUACUGUGUAUAAUAUUUUUAUAUUAUUGGCCUUACCAUAAAAUUAUUUAGAAAGGUUGUCAAAAUAAGUUAUACCUCUUUGGCAAUAGAUAGAUGUAUACAUCUACCUACUAUGAUCUACAAUUUUAGGUUAAGUGAAGCUUGGGGGGGCUACUGACUUGGUUACCUUCUUGUCUCUUGUCCCAAAGAUUUAAACUGUGUACCUUUGUAUAGCUCUUCUGCCCCAUUUUGACUUCUGAGAUGAAAGUAUUUACUAAAAUUAAAAAAAAAAAAACAAAAAACAAACCUUUAGCUCACUAACUUUAUGGGUUUCUGAAGUGAUGGAAAUUUUUAAGGAUAUAUUUAAUAAGCAUAAACUUACUAAUAAUUACUUCCAAAAAUAAAAACAGGAAUAUUACUUUUACCCAGUGUGGUUUAUAGCAUACAUUUGUACUGAAGCAUAUAGGGAUGUUAAUGUGAUCUUUUCCUGACAGAUUAUGAAAGCAUUAUGACUUGUAACAAGUUUCCUUGUAUAUCACUAACAGGUUUAGAAGACAUAAAUAUUAGUGUGUUUUGCCUACAUGGUGUAUUUAAAUCUAUUAAUAUUUUCCUGUUGCUUUUUUAAAAAAAUAAAUACACAUAAUGUAUAUUAAAAGAGGUGGGAUGAAAUAAUUUUAGUAAUUAUGUGUACAGAUGAAACAUUUUUGUCAUGGAAUUUAAAAGCUAAGUAAGUAUAAAAAAUAAAAUGUUAUAUGCAAAAAAUAGGAAACAUGAAAUUGAAAUUUCAUUGUUGGCCAAAAUGAUAUGAGAGAUUUACCUUCCCACCUGAAAUUAAAAAAGAAAAUAUGUGAAA